CUUUGACUCUUACCAUCUCAGAAUUCAAGGUCUAAAUUGACAUAUUUGGGAAGAGCAGGGUGUUGGGGAAACAGAACUGGUAAGUAGAUGGUUUUCCUCUCCCAUCUGACUCAGUGUUAGAGAACUCUGUUGGAGACAGUGUUAAUUUCAAUAUCUUGAUGCCCGAUUUUAUCGUUACAGACAUCCUGUUAUACAGAAUAGCUUAUUUGCUCUCUUAAUAGAAAUCUUGUAAAGAAAAUCCAUCUUCCUUAUUUCACUGUUUCUUUCCCUAAAAGUUUUUGUAUACCACCCCUUUAUCAAGAAUUAAGAUGUUGGGGAAAAAAAAAAAACAAAUCUUUUUGGGCUAAAUAAUGCCAGCUUCACUUCCCUCAAUGAUGACACAUUUAUCUGUAUUUUAAAGUUGUUUUUUUUUUUUUCUCCCUUUCCCACUACACUGCUCUGCAUGUGGGUUCCCUAGCUGAGAAGCUGCCAUUGAUGGUGAAAGACUUUAAUCUAAAUUUAGAUUCUCUUCAGAGGUUUCGUGGAAUACUUCCUUAAAUUAAGCCACAGACUGCAAAAGCUGCUGCUGAGUGGGGCUUCCAGUGUUAUGUGCCAAGAACCUUGCAAAGAAAGACUUCUUCAGGCUCCCUGACCCUUUUGCAAAGAUUGUCGUGGAUGGGUCUGGGCAGUGCCACUCAACCGACACUGUGAAAAACACAUUGGACCCAAAGUGGAACCAGCACUAUGAUCUAUAUGUUGGGAAAACGGAUUCGAUAACCAUUAGCGUGUGGAACCAUAAGAAAAUUCACAAGAAACAGGGAGCUGGCUUCCUGGGCUGUGUGCGGCUGCUCUCCAAUGCCAUCAGCAGAUUAAAAGAUACCGGAUACCAGCGUUUGGAUCUAUGCAAACUAAACCCCUCAGAUACUGAUGCAGUUCGUGGCCAGAUAGUGGUCAGUUUACAGACACGAGACAGAAUAGGAACCGGCGGCUCGGUGGUGGACUGCAGAGGACUGUUAGAAAAUGAAGGAACGGUGUAUGAAGACUCCGGGCCUGGGAGGCCGCUCAGCUGCUUCAUGGAGGAACCAGCCCCUUACACAGAUAGCACCGGUGCUGCUGCUGGAGGAGGGAAUUGCAGGUUCGUGGAGUCCCCAAGUCAAGAUCAAAGACUUCAGGCACAGCGGCUUCGAAACCCUGAUGUGCGAGGUUCACUACAGACGCCCCAGAACCGACCACACGGCCACCAGUCCCCGGAACUGCCCGAAGGCUACGAACAAAGAACAACAGUCCAGGGCCAAGUUUACUUUUUGCAUACACAGACUGGAGUUAGCACGUGGCACGACCCCAGGAUACCAAGUCCCUCGGGGACCAUUCCUGGGGGAGAUGCAGCUUUUCUAUACGAAUUCCUUCUACAAGGCCAUACAUCUGAGCCCAGAGACCUUAACAGUGUGAACUGUGAUGAACUUGGACCACUGCCGCCAGGCUGGGAAGUCAGAAGUACAGUUUCUGGGAGGAUAUAUUUUGUAGAUCAUAAUAACCGAACAACCCAGUUUACAGACCCAAGGUUACACCACAUCAUGAAUCACCAGUGCCAACUCAAGGAGCCCAGCCAGCCGCUGCCACUGCCCAGUGAGGGCUCUCUGGAGGACGAGGAGCUUCCUGCCCAGAGAUACGAAAGAGAUCUAGUCCAGAAGCUGAAAGUCCUCAGACACGAACUGUCGCUUCAGCAGCCCCAAGCUGGUCAUUGCCGCAUCGAAGUGUCCAGAGAAGAAAUCUUUGAGGAGUCUUACCGCCAGAUAAUGAAGAUGCGACCGAAAGACUUGAAAAAACGGCUGAUGGUGAAAUUCCGUGGGGAAGAAGGUUUGGAUUACGGUGGUGUGGCCAGGGAGUGGCUUUACUUGCUGUGCCAUGAAAUGCUGAAUCCUUAUUACGGGCUCUUCCAGUAUUCUACGGACAAUAUUUACAUGUUGCAAAUAAAUCCGGAUUCUUCAAUCAACCCCGACCACUUGUCUUAUUUCCACUUUGUGGGGCGGAUCAUGGGGCUGGCUGUGUUCCAUGGACACUACAUCAACGGGGGCUUCACAGUGCCCUUCUACAAGCAGCUGCUGGGGAAGCCCAUCCAGCUCUCAGAUCUGGAAUCUGUGGACCCAGAGCUGCAUAAGAGCUUGGUGUGGAUCCUAGAGAACGACAUCACGCCUGUACUGGACCACACCUUCUGCGUGGAACACAACGCCUUCGGGCGGAUCCUGCAGCAUGAACUGAAACCCAAUGGCAGAAAUGUGCCAGUCACAGAGGAGAAUAAGAAAGAAUACGUCCGGUUGUAUGUAAACUGGAGGUUUAUGAGAGGAAUCGAAGCCCAGUUCUUAGCUCUGCAGAAGGGGUUCAAUGAGCUCAUCCCUCAACAUCUGCUGAAGCCUUUUGACCAGAAGGAACUGGAGCUGAUCAUAGGCGGCCUGGAUAAAAUAGACUUGAACGACUGGAAGUCGAACACGCGGCUGAAGCACUGUGUGGCCGACAGCAACAUCGUGCGGUGGUUCUGGCAAGCGGUGGAGACGUUCGAUGAAGAAAGGAGGGCCAGGCUCCUGCAGUUUGUGACUGGGUCCACGCGAGUCCCGCUCCAAGGCUUCAAGGCUUUGCAAGGUUCUACAGGCGCGGCAGGGCCCCGGCUGUUCACCAUCCACCUGAUAGACGCGAACACAGACAACCUUCCGAAGGCCCAUACCUGCUUUAACCGGAUCGACAUUCCACCAUAUGAGUCCUAUGAGAAGCUCUACGAGAAGCUGCUGACAGCCGUGGAGGAGACCUGCGGGUUUGCUGUGGAGUGAAAAGCAACCAAAGGCAACAGAGUCUAGCUCAUGGCCACCAGACCAAAAGCAUCCAGCUUCUGUGCACCUCCUGCAAAGCUGGCAGAGGCCCUGGAAUUCCAGAUCACCUGAGGGGAAAGGGUUGUCUCUCUCCUUUCUGUUGGGGGAGGGGGAUGGGGGACUUUUGUUGGUGGCUCCCACCCAUAUAUCCCUCCUUUACCAUAGUACUCCCACCCACUUCCAUCACCCAUCCAAUAAAAUGCAGCCAGGUUUAGCCUUUGGCUUUGGUCACACAGGAUAUUCUGCUGUGUUGCAACCCAUGUGGUGAUAAGGCUCACAGCCCUGAGCUCUUUACGGGAGCAUCAACUCACAGUUAGGGGACUGGGCGUGGCUGAUUGAGGGUUUGGAACUGGUGGCUAUGCCAGCUAUUCCAUCUCAAAACAGCCUUGAGGCCCCUUUUCAAUUUGAGCAGCUGCUAGAUAUCUUAUCAGAGCUCAGAUUCCAGAUUUCACAUCCCAGCAGCCGGUUCUGGGUAGCAGAUCAAUUUCCAACUGGAAAAUAACUAUAUAAUGUAUGCUUAUUGGAAUUCUGCCACAGCAGGAAGCUUGAGUCAAAAUGUGUUUCCCCUUUGAAAGGAGAAGGAAUUGGAGCAGCUUUUCCUGGAGGCCCAGGAUAUUUCUUUUCUGGGUAUCUUGGCUGAAAAUUUUGUUUUACAUAGAGAAAAACGAUCUUUUAAGGGUCCCUUUUGCUGCAUUAUCUGUCCAGUUUGACUUUUUUUUCAGUGAAAACACCAUGUCAUGGAGUGUAGGAAAGAGCAGACCAAAAUCAGCCCUAGAGCCAACCAGUCAGUCCCAAAGCUGUGACCUCUGUGCCACUGUUGUCCAUAGAAGAGCAUCGACUGUGUCACUUAAAAUAUUAGUAAACCAUGAUGCAGCAACUGCUAAGAGCUAAACUAACAAAAUUGUGUCAUCAUAGCUGCUGGCUUGGUGUGAACUCGCUUAAAAGCAAUGGUGAAAGGAUAACCUCGAUGAUGUAAAUCCACCCAAAGAUACUGUUCUACAAAAAGUAGGGUGUGGACGCAAACCUGUGACAGCAGAGGGGGACGACUUCACACUCACUGCCUCAUGUGGCCCCUUUCCCAGUGGCAGCUGGUGACACUAACGAUUGCUACUCGGUUCACUUGCCCAGAUGUCUUCAUAUGAUGAGCAAGGCCAGAAGCAAGGCUAGAUUCGAAGUUUCUGACACCAUUUCCAGUUUGCACAAAAGUCAGUAUUUUAUCUUAAAGUGGCUUGAUUUCCAAUAGCUGAACUUGGGCAGAAAACAGCAGGCCAAUGUUCCUAUGUGGUUUCUUUGUUGUUGUUUUUGUUUGGGGUGGGGGCAAGUACAGGGUAAUUCAUGAGCAAGACAUUUCACUGCUGUCGAAGUCUCUGGGAUCCCGCUGUGGGUCUGAGAUGGCCUGGGAAGGACCUUGUGGACAAUGGUUUUAUCUGUUCUUUUUGUCACUGUUAAUUUCUGGGCUGCUGAGGUUCUAGAAUAGAAGGGCUGCCAAAUGAGGUUUGCUGCAGGAGGAAAGUUUAAUCCCCCAUUCCAAAAGUCCAGGCCAAAUGGUGGGCUUAGCCUCUUUGAAAAGUUCUGCCUUGCCCCCACAGGUGGGCACAUCCUGUGUCUCAUUCACCAUGAUGCUUCCUGAGGGUGUUCUAGAAGCCCGUUCCCCAGUGGCUGUAUCCAGCCUUUCCUUGCAUCAUCUUCCUCUUGAAGGUGAGGAAGUGAAAACUACAGACCUCCCCCGGACAGCCCACUCUCUAUCACGAGCCUAACCCGCGGGAGGCGGAAGAGACAUCCAUUCGAGAACUGAAGCGGCCUCCGGGAUGAGGUCAGAGGCCCCACCUGAUUUUCCUGGUGGUGGUAUCCAAAAUCUUCAGUAACUAGGAAGGAAACCAGGGUCUCAUGGUUUAAAAGACUUUGAAGCAGGAAUGUUGCAUUUGACGCCUUUAAAACUACCUUUUUGCUGUUGGGAGGAGUCGGGGGCGAGCCUUAGCAGCUGCACCGCCAUCCCCAUGCUGGUUGGUGCUGCCCUGCCUCUCGUGCCGGGUGUUGCUUCAGCCCAGAGCCAGAGGGCUGGGUCCCGGGUCCUCCACAGGUGACCCCGGUGGACACACGCGUUCCCAUCCUGGCCUCCGUCUCUGCUUUUCCACUUCUACCUGCGUGUGGGUUUGCCGCCUUGUCAUCGGUUGUGUGAGUGUCGCAGACCUUUCCAGAGCUCCGGUUCACUCUUUCCAAACAGGCCUCCCUGUCGGUGGCACUGCACUCCUAGAACCUUCAGUUUCUACGAUGGUUUGUUUGGUCCUUUUGAACCACCCCAAAGAACUCAACAUGGCAAAGCAAAUGGUAAAAGCUUCCCGACUGUUCUACUUUGGGUCCGCGCGAAGCCCACUCACGUGUGAUCUGUGUUGCCCCUCUCGGUGGUCCCAGGCGAUCCAGCCAUGCCCCCUGCCCCUCUGCCCAGAUGCUUCAGGGGCCCGGCUUUUCAGGCUUGCCCUCACCAGCGGCCGUCAGCCGACACUCAGGGAUGUAGCUAACACCACUCCGCCAGUGCUUUCAGUAGGAAGAGCUGAGGCUGCCUGGGAGGCCCGGGGCGACCGGAAAAGGGCUCUCUCAAGUUCUGAAAAGAGAAUCUGCCACCAGAUCGAAUUUCGACCCCUGAGCUUGUUCGGACGUAUGGUCCAAAUUCAGAUUAAGGUGGUCACCCAACCCGAGAUGUCAGGAAAGGCCUUCUGCAGAGAAAAUGUCCCCCCACCCGCCAUCUGCAGCCAGGUGUGUGCCACACGGCAGCCUUCCCGAAACAUAGUAUGGAUUUUAAAAAUGUGUUUAUUUUUGUUUCUCAACCACUUUAUAACGUAUUUUUUAAUUUAUUUUGUAAUGUCUUGUUUUGAAGUAUUGCUGCUAUCCUUGUUAUCCUUCCCACUGUUUUUAUCACUGAUUUAUUUUGUGAAAGUUGUACACUAAUGUUCUAUGUCAAAAUCAAAAGUAUUUAAUGAAAUACUAGUUCUAUUUAAUGUGGUUAUGGAACCAGCUGGAAACACAAAACAAACAGUGAUUGUACAGCAGGCUGGGCCCAGGAGGUCAGGUUCAUUUUGUUACAUAUGCAAUAAACUCACGACUUUA